CAAAAUUAAGUUAAAACUUGGACUUUAUUACCUAAGUUACUUAUACCUUUGACAAAUGUUGAUAGAAGUUUUCUUUGUAAACUUUUUCACAGGUGAAUGCAAUCUGUACAUUUUCACUAACACUGGACUCUUACAUCUUUUAAUGGAGAAAAUGCACUUUAGGUUACAUGAAGUGUAUUACACACUUUGAAACUGAACUCAAUUGUUUAAUGAUAUUCAAAAAGUGAUGAGCCAUUUACAUGAAAUAGAGAAGUACCUAUAGCAUAAAAUUAAAUAGGAUAUUAAUUAUUGUGCUUUAGGGCAUAAAUUAGACAAUAACCAAGAUCAGAAGAAUAUGCAAUACGGCUACAGUUCAGCCGGAUUAGAUUCAUUAUCAGAAUUUAAACCCCAUUUCUAAGGAAUAAUGCACUGGGUGCUGUCUGACUAGGUAAUAUGGAGGCAAGGAAAUGCUAUAGUUAGGUACCUCUUACUUUAUUGUUGCGGUAUAUCUGUAAUAUGGCUCCUUUUCUUCCUUAACAUUUCUGCAACUUGCCACUUCUUCAUUGAAGUCCAUCUGAAUUCAGGCUCUUCAGAGGGAAAGUGCCCUUUUCCUAGUUCUGUCCCCCUCACUCCCUUUUUGUUCAACGUGUCCAUUAUGCUUCUCAAAGGCACAGUGGAAAUGUGCAAUUCAAGCUGGUGAUGCCUCAGCUCAUAACCAACAGGCCUUUCAAAAAUGACCUUGGAAAAUUUACACUUUAAAAAGUAUGGCUAAGUGAGUCACAUCUUAGAAAAACAUCUGCUUUUUGGAUUUCUUCCAAAGAAUAAUUGUAUUUAUUUGAUACUAACACACAUUGUCUGCCUAAUUUGCUCAACUUUGUCCCUAUUUUACAGAUGAGAAAAUUGAGGAGAAAUAGCUGAUGACUCCAAUAGGUGGCUUUUAUAGCUCCCUUCCAAGACCCAUAAAGCAAAAAUUCUCUUACAAUUAAGUUUAUAUAAAGUAAACGUGAAGAGUCCUAAUAGAGUUAAUAAUGAAAAAAUAUGAAAAAAUACAUCUGAGAGCCAUAUAAGUCUAAAAUGUCCUUAUUGAUAUGCAUAUAAACUGACGUGAUUUCAACUGUAUUUUCCAAUUUUUCCCCUCAGUUAUCUGGAAGUAUUUUGGAUGUGUAUAGCGGUGAACAAGGAAUUUCACCAAUUAACAUGGGGCUUACAAGUGCUUCUUGUCCAAGUAGUCUACCAAUGAAAAGAGAAAUUACAGAAACUGACACUAGAGCUUUAGCAAAAGAGAGACAAAAAAAGGACAACCACAACCUCAUUGAAAGAAGAAGAAGGUAUAAUAUUAAUUACCGAAUCAAGGAGCUUGGCACUCUUAUUCCAAAGUCUAAUGAUCCUGAUAUGCGCUGGAACAAAGGAACCAUUCUAAAAGCAUCAGUGGAGUACAUCAAGUGGCUACAAAAAGAACAACAGAGAGCCCGAGAAUUGGAACACAGACAGAAGAAAUUAGAGCAGGCUAACAGGCGACUUCUACUUCGGAUUCAGGAACUAGAAAUUCAGGCUCGUACUCAUGGUCUGCCAACCCUGGCUUCACUUGGCACGGUUGAUUUAGGUGCUCAUGUCACCAAACAGCAGAGCCAUCCUGAGCAGAAUUCAGUAGACUAUUGCCAACAACUGACUGUGUCUCAGGGGCCAAGCCCUGAGCUCUGUGAUCAAGCUAUAGCCUUUUCUGAUCCUUUGUCAUACUUCACAGAUUUAUCAUUUAGUGCUGCAUUGAAAGAGGAACAAAGAUUGGAUGGCAUGCUAUUGGAUGACACAAUCUCUCCAUUUGGAACAGAUCCUCUGCUAUCUGCCACUUCCCCUGCAGUUUCCAAAGAAAGCAGUAGGAGAAGUAGCUUUAGCUCAGAUGAUGGUGAUGAAUUAUAAGAAAUAAACAGACCCAAUUCAUCAACUGGAAAGCAAUUCUAUGCUGGUGCUAUGCAAUUAUGCUCUGUGUUUCAUAUGUUGCUUUGGCUUAUUUUUUUUCUUAAAGGAAUGUGUUGUUCAUGAAAAACUGAUAGAAGCAACAGAAGAAUUCGCAGGAAGAAAAAUCAUAGUGUUAAUGAAUUAUUGAGGGCGAAAAAAAGGUGUUUUCUUCUUUGACUACGGAGUCCAAAUCCACUUAAAUUCUGUUUUCCUGAAAAGAGGUACAGCAUAAGAAAUAGCUCUUUAUUGAUGUUUUAAAAGCAGCAACUUGGUGGUGUACUACUGGAACUAAUGACUGCAAAGUGUUAAACGACUGAAAUAUACAAACAGUCUCUUAGUUACUCAUUUCCAUCUUCUCUUCAACUUUCACAUCAGUCUUCCGGAAUCAAGAUCAACAUAUCAGGUGGUCAUUGCCUUUCUCCAUUGUCUAGUAGACAUGUCUAAAGUUCAAACUUUAUAGGAUAAAUAAAUGUAUAAUAGAUUAUCUGUCACUUGUGGUUGAAAGGCAAAUCUACAAUAAAUGUGAGAAUUUUCCACAAUAAAAUAUGGAUAACUUAUAAAAACAUUGGUUACUAAAAUUAGAUCCUCAUUUUAUUGUAGUUGGUUCAAUUACACUAAUUCUAAAAGCAUCCAUGCAUAUUUAUAUCUCCAGUCUCUGUUCAGGAAAAGGAACAUAUUGAAUAUUUUCCUCAGGAAUAUGGACCAGAAUUGUAUCCCUUCACACAAACAUACACAUACACAUAUGCACAUCAUUCAGGUAGUAUAUGUUCUUUUGUUUUCUUCAUGCUUCUGACUGCAUCAGAAUCACAUUCCAAAUUCUCUUUUCUUAUGAAGAAGAGAUGUCAGAUCAUCAAUUUUAGUAAAUAAAAUAUAAAAUGUCCCCCUGCAAGGACAGUUUUCAGGUACUUAAAACUUUUCAUCAGUAUUGGACAGAAAUCAAUUAGUUGUUGAUUUGGUUUUUCUCCAAAUGGAUAAAAUAUUGAAAAUUGAAUUGCCAAUUGACAAAAUAAUUAUUACAACAAACUAUUUCUUAUUAUUUUCAGUUCUGAGAGGAACGUAAGGUUCUAUUUCUAUAAACACUUAGAGUGUCCUAUGAUCUUUGGUUGCACUGUUAGCAUUUAUUAUAAGCACUUAUAACUAUGAUGCUUCAUUUAGAUUUUUAUCUCUUGCGCUUGUUUUAGGUUAGGAAAUUAAGUUACCAAGCACGUUGCUCUGUGCUGGACCUCCAAGAGUGAUCAUCCGAUCAAUGAGUAUUCAUGGAGGCAUACUCAGAACUGCAGUGAGUCCUGAGAAAAUGUAGAAGAGUUGAAAAAGAUAUGGUCUUACUCCUAAGGUAGUUAAUGAGAAUGCAUGAAAAACAAAAACAAAAGAUAGAAGACAUAUAGAAUAAAAAAUCUAAGCAUAAACUGUAAAUACAGAAGGUCAGAGAAAAUGAAAAUGACUGACAAACUUUAUGGGAACAGCAGAAUUUGACUUCUCUUUGAAAGGCAUUAAUUGAGUGAAAGUGAGGGCAUAUAAAGGAAUAAUACCAACCAAAUGAUAAAAGUGAGAAUAAUAGGGGAAGUAUCUUUAUAGGACUUUAAUUAGAAAGAUCUGGAUGCCCUAGAAGAUGUCUGUUGGGGAGUUCUGAAGCAUAAGACUGACAACAGGUUGUGAAGGCCCUUAGAAAACUAUGGUGAAAUAAUAUAGUAUUAAUAUAAUAGAAACAAAUCUUUUUAGUAGCAGGGAGGAUGCUAAAAACUAAAAUAUAUAUUACUAAUGAGUGAGAUGUAAUCUUUCAUGAAUAUUAAGCUUUGGGAUAAAUUUUGAAAGGAUCUUUUAGUUGCUUCUCACAUGGAAAAUAUGUCACUAUGAAAUGUGAGACCCUAAUGCUGAUAAAAGUAGAAAAAUAGUAAAUCAUUAUGGUAUAAUAAUUAUCUCAGGCUUAGCUUGUAUCAUUUGCUCAGAAUUUGGAGAAUUAAAAUAAUUUUAUUGUUUGACAUGGAAAAAUAAUUACUAACUUCUGGGUACAGUCAUUAAAGCCUGAUAGAUAAAUUCAUCUGAAAUAUGCCAUGUGAAACAGCUAUUAGAUACAUCUUCUCAAUAAUUUUCAAGACGAUAUUACAUACUUUUAAUUUUAUAACAAAAUUCCACUUCAUUAUCUGAGUUGAUAAUUUGAUUAAAUGUUAAAAAUUAUAGAUAAGGAAUAUAUUUUGGAGUUCAUAGAAAACACACCACUUUAUUAGAUAGAGACUGGCUUCAGUUCUCAUUUUAUCUGCUCUUCUCAUUUCUUCAUAUUUUGAGUAGACUUGCACUGAUGAUGUCAUUACUCAGUCAUUAUUUUCUGUUCUGUUAAGGUACAACUACUGGGCCUUGAAAUCUAUCCUUCACAAUCUUGGCUGAGAUAAGGACUUGGCACAGGAUGAUAGAGCCUGGACACAAGAGAUCUGGAGAGGGAACUGCUAUUUGCUGCUACAUUCAGAUUAUGAGAUGUCAGGGAACUGUAAAAAGGGUAAUGAAUUUUUAAAGAGAGUAAAGAGUUAUGCUGUGUCCCGGUCAACUGAAAUACAUUAAAAAUUAAUUAGAUGGUAGUUCUUAACUUUUUAAGGCAGAUACCUUGAGAAUCUAGUGAGUUAUAGACCCUCUCCCUAGAAAAGUAUAGAACUGUUUAUAUGGACAAUAAUUCACAUGCAUUCAGAGAUCUUAGGGAUCUCCUGAAUGUUUUCUUGGAUCCCAAGUGAAAAAUUCCUGAAUCAGGUCUCUUAGGUGUGCGGUUAAUGUCAUGUAUAACAAUGGGGGGACCCUUACUUAUCUAAAUAUAAUUAUCCCAAUCCUAAUAAUGAUGAGGUUGCAUAGGAAAGUAAUAGUGUACCAAACUUUAGAUUAUUCACUAAAAAAGUUGUUCAUUUAUGAAGUAGUCGUUUAUCAAACAUGUCCUCCCCACUCAGCAAACUAUGCCUUCUAUUUAUUAUAUAUGGGUCAGUUUCACUAUAAUUACUGAGUGUUAUAAACAUCUGACCAUAACAUUUUGAAAUGAUGCAAAUAAAUUUCCAAACAAAAAUAGUGUGAAUUUAAAAGCAAAUUAUUUGAGUAUCUAAGAAACAAGAUAGACUUCUAGAAAAAUUUGACUCUCUAGAAUAUUUCUUGCAGAAAUGAGAUUUUUCAUAAUAGUAAAAGAGGCAUAUGUUUAUCAAACAAUGCUGUCACAAAAAGCAUCAACUGUAAUGGGACUAUUAAUGCAUAAUUAUUGAUUUAUUCAUUCAAUUAAUAUACAAUUAUCCCUUUUCAUUUAAAGAUUUAAUUCAUAAUUACAAUUAUAAUAAAACUUCCUUUAAAGUAAGAUACAAUAAUUUUAUUGUUUUUCAUUCUUUUUUCAACAAAAUAUCCCAUCCAAUCAUUUUUUAUAUUAUUAAAUAUUGGCUGCUUUUUCUUGGAUUCACAUUAAACAGCCCUUUCCAACUUCCAAUUGUCUUAAAAUAAUGAUGACCUCCUGUGAGUAGAUACAGCUCUUUACAAUUUUUUUCUUUAGUGCCUUUUCUUCUUGAAUUUUUCCUAUAUCAAAUGGAGAAUAUAUGUACAGAUGGUAUUUUCUCAGUUUAUAGGCAUAUCAGUGACCAUGGCUUUCUUUAUAUAGGUUUUUAAAAAAGCCCUAAAUAAUAAAUAGCCAGAUGAGCUGGGGACAUUGAGAAAUAGCCUUCCUCUUCCUUUUUCAACUCAUUUUUUUCCCACCUACAUGACUGUAAAUCAAAUAUUUAAUAGCUCUUACUUAAAAAAACAGAUACAAAGAAUGUCUUGAUUUGGUGUGCUCAUUUACCAUAAUGUCAUGAGGGGAAUUAGAUUUCACAACUUUAAAAGGAAUAUAUUUUUAUUUUAUUUUGAAAAACUGAGUCAUAUAGGAAUUUUCUUAUACUUCAAGGCAUCAUGGAAACACUUUUUUCCUGUUUGGAUAUUGUGGAAUUUAAACGUUCAAAUAAAUAAAUGGCAUAACUAAGUGUUCCAAAUUUUUUUACAAUGUCUUUGACCCUAUUCAAACACUUUAGGUAUUUACUGACCGUCUGAUGUGUAAGAUGUGGAAUAAAACUGGAAUCAAUUAAUUAUUUCACUGUGUUAUCAGCGCAAGAUCAACCAUCUGGGUUUCUUAAAGACACCCGAAGGAUUGAAUUUUGUUUCAGUAUUGAUAAUGGCAUAGUCUCUAUGUGCUACAUGGAAUUACAUCAUUUAUCCCUCCAGUGCCCUAUAUGUUGAUAAGUAUGUCAGUUUGACUUAGUAUACAUAUAUACAGAGAUUUCAUUACAUUUACCUAAUAAAUACAAAAUACAUUUCGAGUGUUACUGAUCUCCUAUGUUACAUGAGCCUCCUGUAAUCAUUGUGCAUUGAUGUUCCAAUGUUUUAUUGUUUGUAUGAAUUUUAAUUUGAAAACAAGGAAACAAUCCAAAAGCAGAAAAAAUAGCUUUUCUUAAAAUUUUCAGUGCUACAUUUUCCCUCUGAGGUCCAUAGAGAUUUGAAUGUAUAGGAGAUUAUCCGAAAACAGCUAUUUUGAUUAAAAAAUAUAUCUCCCAGGAUUCAACCAACUUAAUGAUGAAGUACUAUUGUCUACUGCUUUAUACAUAAAAGGGAACUUUUUAUCUGCUUGUAAAGGGAUUUUUAUGUGUAUUUCUGCAUAAUCAGAUGACUUCUAUUGUGUUUUCUACUGAUGAAAUUCUCUGUAAAAUGUCUUUUUCUUACAUUAUCCAACAGGCAUAAAGAAUAACAGUAAAGACUUUUGUGUUUGUAAUACUACCUCUUUUAUCCCUGCACUACUGUUUUAUUGCAAAAAUUCUAUAUUGUCACUGUAUUUUUUCCAUAGAAUAUAAAUUUUGUUCUUGUGCUAAAGCUGGUAGUUUAUGUAGCAGACAAAAUAUACAAAUAAAAGAAGAGACUGAUUUUGCUGAAAGAAUUAUAUAUAAUCAAGAAGUUACAUAUUGUUCUUUAAAUAUGAUACUGAAUUUUAAAAGCAAACGAAAUUCAAGAAUCUUAUCUAACAGCAUAGCAGUUGCUUAUGGCAUACAAGGCUAAAAUUAAUUCAGCUAUUUAAUCUUAAUAAUUAUUAUGUAGUUAAAAAUCUUUGACUUUAAUAGUGUUUUACAUAUACAAAUAGCUGAAGUAACAUUCCUAUAAUUUUAAUCUGACAUUGGUUAGAUCAAGAAAACAUUGUUAAUAAGACUGUAGAAUUUGUAAUUAUUGCUAUUUUUCAUUUUUAAUAACAAAGUAAUGUGUCUUAUUUUCUAAGAAAAUGGAGAACUUUGGUGUACUUUAAUACAUACAAAAAUCUUUGUAAAAAUACCUUAAAAUGUACCAAUAUUUUCUUUGCAUAUAUUAAAUGAAAGACUAUAAUUAUGAAA